CUUGACCAUGGUCCGCCGUCCUCUGGGAGCUGAGGGAGAUGUCCUCGGGUUGUGUAGAUGAGAGGAUGCCGUCCGGGCUGCGGGUUCCCCGGGCUUGUUUCCUCAGAGAUGCGCCCCUUCCUCUUGGAAGGCGGGAAAGCAAAGUGUGUCCCAGAUGCCUGUGGCCGAGGGCAAGAGUGUUCAGCAAACCGUAGAGCUCCUUACCCGGAAAUUGGAGAUGCUUGGGGCAGAGAAGCAAGGAACAUUUUGUGUGGACUGUGAGACUUACCAUACGGCCGCCUCUACCCUUGGCAGCCAAGGGUCUCUCUGUCACCCAGGCUGGAGUGCAAUGGCAUGAUCAUAGCUCACUAUUGCCUCGACCUGCCGGGCUCAAGUGAUCCUCCAGCCCCAGCAUCCUAAAUAGCUGGGGCCACAGGUCAGACCGGGAAGCUGAUGUAUGUGAUGCACAACUCAGAGUACCCAUUGAGCUGUUUCGCCCUCUUUGAGAAUGGCCCUUGCCUUAUUGCUGACACCAACUUUGAUGUGCUUAUGGUGAAGCUCAAGGGCUUUUUCCAGAGUGCUAAGGCCAGCAAGAUUGAGACCCGGGGCACCAGGUACCAGUACUGUGACUUCCUGGUGAAGGUGGGCACGGUCACAAUGGGGCCCAGUGCCCGGGGCAUCUCUGUGGAGGUGGAGUAUGGCCCCUGUGUGGUAGCUAGUGACUGCUGGAGUCUGCUGCUCGAGUUCCUACAGAGUUUUCUAGGCAGCCACACACCAGGGGCUCCCGCAGUGUUUGGGAACAGACAUGAUGCGGUCUACGGCCCAGCAGAUACCAUGGUCCAGUACAUGGAACUCUUCAACAAGAUCCGCAAGCAGCAGCAGGUGCCGGUGGCUGGGAUUCGUUAGUGAUGAGCAGCUGCCAGCUGAGCUCUGUCACCAGGGGUACUCCACAGGAGGAGCAGGUGCUGACUUUCAGGUCCCUGGACCCCAGAAACCCAGGGUAGACAUGGACUCUACUCUCCUUCUCUGGUUCUCAGCUGUGGCUUUUGUUCUGGGGCUGAGUCCCCUCCCCAACCCCCUGACUCUCACACAUAGCCCCCCAUCAGCUGUUUUACUCCGUGCCUUACUGGAUUUGGCCUGUCCUCAAGAAUGGUAAUUAUGAAGAGUGGAGAAGUUUGGACCUUGCCUCCUUUAGGGGAAAGGUAGGACAGGAAUGUCCCUGCCUGGUACUGGUGGGGGAAAUAGUCCGUAUCCCCAACUAUUAAGGAUUUGUCCCAGGCCAAUGGUGAACAUGCUGCAUUUUAUGUUUGGAUUGUGCUGUAAUAAGAGCCUCUUCCUUCCCUCAGAGGAUGUGGCUGGGCUUCUAUCCUAGAGAUGGAGUAGAAGGCACAACUGGUUUGAUAGUUACUAUUUUCUGACCUGUUUGCUGAAGUGAUUUGCGAAUUGACUUUCCUAGGGUGUUGCCUGAGUCCUUUGAAAUCUCCUUCUGACAUCUUUCCCUUCUGUUGUGAAAUAUGUUAAGCCACAGGCCAAACUGCUAUAAGAUCGAAGUUUGUUUUUUUCUCACCUAAUAAUAGAGAGGUAAUCAGAUGGUCUAGGGCAGAUUUAACUCUACAAGGUUAUCAGGAACUUUGUUUCCUUCUGUCUUAUUCAGCCAUUCCCAGUAUGUUUUCUUACCCAUAAGAUCAAAGCAGACUCAUCAGCUCCAUAUCUGCAUUCCACUGGGGAAAGAGAGAGAGAAAAGAGCAGAUUUUAAAAAAAAGAUAUGACUGAGCAUUGCUCAGAUCACUGUGGCCACACUUUGCUGAAAGAGAUGCUGGGACAUAGAACCUCUUAUCUGGGCAGUCAUGUGCUGAGUUAAAACUCAGGGAUUCUGUGACUACAAGAUGAAAGACAAUUUGGUUGCUGAGAUGCAGUUAAUGGCUUCUGUUACAUGGAGCUCAAUGGACGUGCCCAGGAAUGCUUUUGGCUGUUAUUUUGCAGUUAAUACCUCCUGUAACUAAAGCAUUUGUUUAUGAGUUGACUUGAGAGAAGGGCUGAUCUCAGAGCCGCUUUGAGCUAAGUUGGAUUAGUCACACUAGGAAGUUAAUUCCACACCUUUCGUCUAAGUCUCAGUAUUGAGGCCUCUCCAGUUCUCAUGCACCCUGAUCUUAGGGUUAGAAUACUUGACCCUGAUACCUGCACCAUGCUUCAUGGUUCCUGAGCUCUUUCUCCUGUUUCAUUUGAGCCUCCAAACUACAUAUUUGGUCAUAUUGCCUGCCUACCCCAUGCCUGCUGCAGAAAUAUUCAUCCAGGUUAACCUUGAUAUACACAGAGAUGGUCUUGGAGAAUUGUGAAUGUAUGUACUGUAUUGUCAUCAAGGAUACUGUCCCUUAUUUGAAGGCAUCUAAAGAGAAACUGUUUUCAGAUCCAAGUGCUCAGAUCUAAAGCCUCUGCAACAAGUCAGGUGGUGGUCAUGUUUCCCUUCUAGUUUUGGCUGACAGGAAGCUCAGUUCAGUACCAUAACUACAGAACCUGUCAUCUGUAUUUUUUGUUCUCACCCCGUUUUUGUUAUUUUGUUUCUGGUUUUUUAUAUUGAGGUAUGUUUUAGAUAUAGUUUACAAAAAUAAAACGCACAGAUCUUA